GCGCUAGUGUUGGGUGUUCCGCUGUGCUGUUUUUCCGUCAUGGCUCGCACUAAGCAAACUGCUCGGAAGUCUACUGGUGGCAAGGCGCCACGCAAACAGUUGGCCACUAAGGCAGCCCGCAAAAGCGCUCCGGCCACCGGCGGCGUGAAAAAGCCCCACCGCUACCGGCCGGGCACCGUGGCUCUGCGCGAGAUCCGCCGUUAUCAGAAGUCCACUGAACUGCUUAUUCGUAAACUACCUUUCCAGCGCCUGGUGCGCGAGAUUGCGCAGGACUUUAAAACAGACCUGCGUUUCCAGAGCUCCGCUGUGAUGGCUCUGCAGGAGGCGUGCGAGGCCUACUUGGUAGGGCUAUUUGAGGACACUAACCUGUGCGCCAUCCACGCCAAGCGCGUCACUAUCAUGCCCAAGGACAUCCAGCUCGCCCGCCGCAUCCGCGGAGAGAGGGCGUGAUUACUGUGGUCUCUCUGACGGUCCAAGCAAAGGCUCUUUUCAGAGCCACCACCUUUUC